AGUCCGCGCGGGUUCUCGCGCGGAGAAGGGGUGCGAGCGGCGGCGGCGGCGGAGGCUGCCAUGGACGACGAGGAGGAGACGUACCGGCUCUGGAAAAUCCGCAAGACCAUCAUGCAGCUGUGCCACGACCGUGGCUAUCUGGUGACCCAGGACGAGCUUGACCAGACCCUGGAGGAGUUCAAAGCCCAAUCUGGGGACAAGCCGAGUGAGGGGCGGCCGCGGCGCACGGACCUCACCGUGCUGGUGGCCCACAACGAUGACCCCACCGACCAGAUGUUUGUGUUCUUUCCAGAGGAGCCCAAGGUGGGCAUCAAGACCAUCAAGGUGUACUGCCAGCGCAUGCAGGAGGAGAACAUCACACGGGCUCUCAUCGUGGUGCAGCAGGGCAUGACACCCUCCGCCAAGCAGUCCCUGGUCGACAUGGCCCCCAAGUACAUCCUGGAGCAGUUUCUGCAGCAGGAGCUGCUCAUCAACAUCACGGAGCACGAGCUAGUCCCUGAGCACGUCGUCAUGACCAAGGAGGAGGUGACAGAGCUGCUGGCCCGAUACAGUAAGCUCCGAGAGAACCAGCUGCCCAGGAUCCAGGCGGGGGACCCUGUGGCGCGCUACUUUGGGAUAAAGCGUGGGCAGGUGGUGAAGAUCAUCCGGCCCAGUGAGACGGCUGGCAGGUACAUCACCUACCGGCUGGUGCAGUAGCUACCGCCUGACAGCCCCUAGAGGCGGACACACAGCGACCCCCAUCCCUGCAGGACAAACGCCCCUGCCCUGCCAGAAUCCGGCCCCCACAGCUCUCACGGCUGCUGCUCCUCUGGACUCCCCAAGGCAGGUGGCCUCCACCCACGUUCUCCCGUCCUGGGGUGAGGCUUCCUGUGGCCCAGCCCGCCCCAUUCACCUGUGGAUUUGUGCGAGAUGCAGCCUCAGAAGGAACAAGGCCCCCAGAGGGAGGUCACCUGGGGGCAGCUGGUGCCGGGUCUUCACCCAGACCACGCUGGGUCCCCUCUGUUGGGGGUUUGGGGUCCGGGUCUCCCACCAGCCACUGCUUCCUCCUGGGCCCUCGGCCUUCCACCCCUCGUCUUCCCUCCCUCGGGGGCCCUGAUGCGUGGCGGCCCCCGCCCGGCCUCGGCUCUUUACUCCAUUCACAGCCAUGCACGCGCUCAAGCCACCAGGGUGCGAGAUGCCAGCUCUGGAGUUCUCGGUUGUUGUAGGAGGUUGGGUGUUUUCAAAUGGUAAAGAUGUUUUGAGCAAAUAAAUUUGCUUGAUACAGAAACCAGGCCGACUAACAAGGUUUCCAGCAGGUGGCCUUGCCUCACCCCAAGCACACGAGGUCAGCCUGGCAGGUGUGCCCUCCUCGCGCUGGCUUCAGGGGUCAGUGUCUCCCCAGGCCCUCGCCCUGCCCUCCCACUUCGUGCUCCUGGGUAAGGCGUGAGCGUGUCUGUCUCUUCCCUUCCCGUGAGGGUGUGGAGUUGUUCUCUGGCUUGUGCAGCUGUGGUUUGCGGCCAGUUCCUCUUACAGACGUUUGGGAUCUGGCUCUACUUCCCCGUUUGCUUACUGUCUGAUUUCAGAAGGCCUCGCCUGCCCAAGUUUAACCUAGCCACGUGGUUCUCUCACAGUAGCUUUAUUAAGAUGUAAUUCACCCUCGGGCGGUCGGUGGUCUGUAACGCGCCCACUGUUCUGUGCAGCAGGGUCCCCAGAUCCCCAGGCCGCGGACUGUGUGUGUGAUGGGGACAGUGCUUCCCCUUCUCUCCAAAUGUACUUUUUUCAAAAUUGUCUUGGCCAAAGCAAGCCAGACCCAAAGGGACAAACACUGAUGUCACUCCUAGGAGGUCACUAGAGUCGUCAGAGACUGGAAGUAGGAUGGGGGUUCCCGGGACUGGGGAGUUGGGUGGGGAUGGGGGUUCCCAGGGCUGGGGAGGAGGGAGGGGACAGAGUGUGUCAUGUGCACAGUUUUAGUUUGGGAAGAUGAGAAAAUUCUGGAGGUGGCCGGGCGCGGUGGCUCACGCCUGUAAUCCCAGCACUUUGGGAGGCCGAGGUGGGCGGAUCACCUGAGGUCGGGAGUUCGAGACCAGCCUGACCAACAUGGCAAAAUCCCAUCACUGCAAAAAAUACAAAAAUUACCUGGGCGUGGUGGUGCAUGCCUGUAAUCCCAGCUACUUGGGAGCUAAGGCAGGAGAAUCACUUGAACCCAGGAAGUGGAGGAUCGCUUGAGCUCAGGAGUUAAAAGACCAGCCCGGGCAACACAGAGAAACCCCCCACCUCUACAAAAAACUUUAAGAUUACCUGGGCACAGUGGCUCACACCUGUAAUCCCAACACUUUGGGAGGCUGAGGCGGGAGGAUCAUUUGAGCCCAGGAGGCCGAGGCUGCAGUGAGCUACGAUUGUGCUCCUGUACUCCAGCCUGGGCCACAGGGUCACACCCUGUCUCAAAAAAAAAAAAAAAUGCAGUUCCACAGGCGCAUGGGCCACGUUUCCAGUGCUUGGUGGCCAUGUGGGGCUGACGUGCGAAACCUUAGAGCCGGGGGAUACGUCCGUCAUCGAGAACGUUUUCCUGGACUGCCCUGGGCUGCAGGUGGACGUGACGAGGUCAUUCGAUGCCUGACCGUCUGCACAGCCUGUGGUGAAGACCACCCGGGCUCCCACCUCGCGGGGCCCCGUGGCGGGGGGUUCCCUUCCUCACACAUCCCUCCCCUAGGGGGAGGCCCAGGGCCACGCCACGGGGCUCUCUCUGUCCCCUCCCUGGCCCCUUCUUCUAAGCUUGCAGCUGCCACAGAAAAUCUUCUAAGCUUGCAGCUGCCACAGAAAACACCCGAUUAAAAACUUUUUAUUUCAGCAAAAUAAACGUGCCUGUGAAAGAACCACA